AAAGAAAAAAAAAAAAGAAAAAAGAAAUACGGAAUUCCAGGCCCUGUCCUGUCCAAGACCUCCUGAAACACAAUCAGCAAUUUGAUAAGGUCUCCAGGGAAUGAUUUACACGGUAAAAUCUGGGAAGUGCUGGUUUGUCAAGAACCUUCAGGAUCACAUCUGUGCUCUUCACAAACAUCGCUUGGAUUAAAAAGGGGGGAAGGGGCAGAGCCGUCCAUGGUUACAGUUCUGUUCCAAGAUAAAUAUACGCUUUCCUCUGCGCUGAUUUUUUUCUGAUGAGAAGACCAGAAUAUUUAUGCAACUCCCUUGAGUAGUUAUAUAUUUAUAGGGGCAGGCAGUGGUCAACAGUGGCCCGAACCAUUGGACUCCUUGCUCAAAACUGCCUCAGCUCAUCUGCCUGAAAUUCCAGUUACUGUCAUGUUGUGGGGACCCAUAUAGGAACAAAACGUGGACUACUCGAGAGGUAGCUACCCUGCGCCCACAGACUGUGACAACGGAGGGUGACCCAGGAGGGGAAGCUGCCUCUCUUCCGGCCUAGGAUCCAUUGUCAUCUGCAGAGAGAGAAGUGCCAAGGGAUCCUCAGAGAUACCAUGACUGCAGCACCAACCAAAAUCCACCCAGACAGCCAACUUUCCCGGAGCACUGUUAUGUCUUUUCGGGCUGAGAUGACUCAAGAAGAAAUGUCCCUGAUCCUUGUCCAUCUCCAGGCUUGGGAGAAGGUUGUAAAGAAAUGUGGCUUCGAAAGUGAUGAGGCUGGUAUGCUGUCCUACUUUCUGUUUGAAGAGCUGAUGCGAUGUGACAAAGAUUCCAUGCCAGAUGGAAAUCUGUCAGAGGAGGAAAAAUUGUUUCUCUCAUAUUUUCCUUUGCACAAGUUUGAGCUAGAACAGAACAUCAAAGAACUUAACACCCUUGCGGACCAAGUUGACACCACUCACGAGUUGCUUACCAAGACCAGCCUGGUGGCCAGCUCUUCCGGGGCUGUUUCUGGGGUCAUGAACAUCCUGGGUUUGGCCCUAGCACCUGUGACAGCAGGAGGCAGUCUCAUGCUCUCAGCAACUGGGACAGGGUUGGGGGCAGCAGCUGCCAUCACCAACAUAGUAACAAAUGUCUUAGAAAAUAGAAGCAAUUCAGCAGCAAGAGACAAAGCCAGCCGACUGGGGCCUCUGACAACAUCACAUGAGGCUUUCGGAGGAAUAAAUUGGUCUGAAAUCGAGGCUGCUGGCUUUUGUGUUAAUAAGUGUGUAAAAGCUAUCCAGGGCAUCAAGGAUCUUCAUGCCUACCAGAUGGCCAAAUCCAACUCUGGCUUCAUGGCUAUGGUCAAGAAUUUUGUGGCCAAGAGACACAUCCCUUUCUGGACGGCUAGAGGGGUGCAGAGAGCCUUUGAGGGCACAACUCUGGCCAUGACCAAUGGUGCCUGGGUGAUGGGUGCUGCUGGGGCUGGCUUCUUACUUAUGAAAGACAUGAGCAGCUUCCUGCAGAGCUGGAAGCACCUGGAGGAUGGGGCAAGGACGGAGACAGCAGAGGAACUGAGAGCACUUGCUAAGAAGCUGGAGCAGGAGCUGGACCGGCUCACCCAGCACCACCGGCACCUGCCGCAGAAGGCGAGCCAGACCUGUUCCAGCUCCCGGGGCAGGGCUGUUCGAGGAUCCCGUGUGGUUAAACCAGAAGGGUCUCGCUCACCUCUCCCCUGGCCUGUUGUGGAGCACCAGCCUAGGCUGGGCCCUGGCGUGGCACUGAGGACACCAAAGAGGACAGUCUCUGCCCCAAGGAUGCUUGGCCACCAGCCAGCCCCACCAGCACCAGCAAGAAAGGGGAGACAGGCCCCGGGAAGACACCGACAAUGAGAAGAGUUGGUCACCCUGUCACCACUGAACCUUGAUUUAACAGAGGCAAAAUGCAAGUCUUCCCUGAAGAAUACUGGGGGUAGGGAAACUUCUAGUGGCAAUGAUAAAACCAGCAGCAAUGAUAAUAGAAGGCAAA